AGUCCCUUGUUCCCCGCCGCCGCCGUCGCUGACCCAGCCCGCCAGGCGCUCCUGACCGUCGCUUCCUCCGGUCCCAGGUCCCCGGCCCUCGCCUCAGCCCCGGCCCCUGGUCCCCAGCCCUCGUCGCAGCCCCGGCCGCCCGCCGCCGCCAUGUCCAAGGAGGAGCGCCCCGGUCGGGAGGAGAUCCUGGAGUGCCAGGUGAUGUGGGAGCCUGACAGUAAGAAGAACACGCAGAUGGACCGCUUCCGGGCGGCUGUGGGCGCCGCCUGCGGCCUGGCGCUGGAGAGUUAUGAUGACUUGUACCAUUGGUCCGUUGAGUCAUAUUCAGACUUCUGGGCAGAGUUCUGGAAAUUCAGUGGAAUUGUCUUCUCACGUGUGUAUGAUGAGGUUGUGGACACAUCGAAAGGAAUCGCAGAUGUCCCCGAGUGGUUCAAAGGCAGUCGGCUCAACUAUGCAGAAAACCUCCUGCGGCACAAAGAGAAUGACAGAGUUGCCCUUUACAUUGCAAGGGAAGGCAAAGAGGAAAUUGUGAAGGUGACUUUUGAAGAGCUGAGGCAAGAAGUGGCUUUGUUUGCAGCAGCAAUGAGGAAAAUGGGUGUGAAGAAAGGAGAUCGGGUUGUUGGUUAUUUACCCAACAGUGAGCACGCUGUCGAGGCGAUGCUGGCUGCGGCAAGCAUUGGUGCCAUCUGGAGCUCCACGUCCCCGGACUUCGGUGUGAAUGGUGUGCUGGACCGGUUUUCUCAAAUUCAGCCAAAGCUCAUCUUCUCUGUGGAGGCUGUUGUCUAUAAUGGCAAAGAGCACAACCACAUGGAAAAGCUGCAGCAGGUGGUUAAAGGCCUACCAGACUUGAAGAAAGUGGUGGUGAUUCCUUAUGUGUCCUCCAGAGAGAACAUAGACCUUUCAAAGAUUCCAAACAGUGUGUUUCUGGAUGACUUUCUUGCCACCGGCACCAGUGAGCAGGCCCCGCAGCUGGAGUUCGAGCAGCUGCCCUUCAGCCACCCACUGUUCAUCAUGUUCUCAUCGGGCACCACGGGCGCACCCAAGUGCAUGGUGCAUUCCGCUGGGGGCACCCUCAUCCAGCAUCUGAAGGAGCACCUGCUGCACGGCAACAUGACCAGCAGUGACAUCCUCCUGUGCUACACCACGGUCGGCUGGAUGAUGUGGAACUGGAUGGUGUCCCUUCUGGCCACAGGAGCGGCCAUGGUCUUGUACGAUGGCUCCCCCCUGGUGCCCACGCCCAAUGUGCUCUGGGACCUGGUUGACAGGAUAGGCAUCACUGUCCUGGUAACUGGGGCCAAGUGGCUGUCAGUGCUGGAAGAGAAGGCCAUGAAGCCGGUGGAAACCCACAGUCUCCAGAUGCUCCACACGAUCCUGUCCACUGGCUCCCCACUGAAAGCCCAGAGCUACGAGUAUGUCUACAGGUGCAUCAAGAGCAGCAUCCUCCUGGGCUCCAUCUCAGGAGGCACCGACAUCAUCUCCUGCUUCAUGGGCCACAAUUUUUCUCUUCCUGUGUAUAAAGGGGAGAUUCAGGCCCGGAACCUGGGCAUGGCCGUGGAAGCGUGGAACGAGGAAGGAAAGGCGGUCUGGGGAGAGAGCGGCGAGCUGGUGUGUACUAAGCCGAUCCCUUGCCAGCCCACACACUUCUGGAACGAUGAGAACGGCAACAAGUACAGGAAGGCGUAUUUCUCCAAAUUCCCAGGUAUCUGGGCUCAUGGCGACUACUGCAGAAUCAACCCCAAGACCGGGGGCAUCGUCAUGCUUGGCCGGAGUGACGGCACCCUCAACCCCAACGGGGUGCGGUUCGGCAGCUCGGAAAUCUAUAACAUUGUGGAAUCCUUCGAGGAGGUGGAGGACAGCCUGUGUGUCCCCCAGUAUAACAAGUACAGGGAGGAGAGGGUGAUCCUCUUCCUGAAGAUGGCCUCCGGGCACGCCUUCCAGCCUGACUUGGUUAAGAGGAUCCGUGACGCCAUCCGCAUGGGCUUGUCUGCGCGACACGUGCCCAGCCUCAUCCUGGAAACCAAGGGCAUCCCGGUAUGGCCAUCUCCCGCCAGCGAGGAGACCGCAGCCAUCGCCCCACGAGCCCACACAUUGAGGGGCGCUUACAUCUGAGCAGCUUGCCGGUGCUUUAUAUAUCGUUUGUCCACGUUGCCUAGCAACGCCAUCCUCUCCCUGCCAUCCUUUUUCCUACCCUUCCUAAGACUGCAUUUAAAGCAACUUCUGCUAAAUACCCAUGUUCAGAGGGUUAGCAGGCCCAGCCCUGCAGGUCCAACUGGCUUCUCCCUGCUAUCCCCUGGUUUUAGUGUAUUCUCAAAAUUUUUAAUGAGAACAUUAAUUUUAACUUUUUAUUUUUUAUUUUAUUUUUUUGAGACUGAGUCUGUCACCCAGGCUGGAAUGCAAUGGCUCAAUCUCAGCUCACUGCAACCUCCGCUUCCCAGGUUCAAGCAGUUCUCCUGCCUCAGCCUCCUGAGUUAACUGGUAGCUGGGAUUACAGUCACAUGCCAGCAUGCCUGGCUAAUUUUUGUAUUCUUAGUAAAGAUGGGGUUUUGCCAUGUUGGCCAGGCUGGUUUCAAACUCCUGACCUCAAGUGAUCCGCCCACCUCAGCCUCCCAAAGUGCUGGGAUUACAGGCGUAAGCCACUCUACCCAGCCAAUUUUAACUUUUUAAAGUGCUGCUGGGAGCCGUUGCUGUUGCCUUUUAGUUUUAAGUUCUGCUGGUACAGACAAGACUUGACUCUUUUUAGAGGCAGGUCUUCCUAAGGCUGUGUCGUCAUCCCCCAGCCCCUGGCCCCAGUACGCUCUGCUUUGAUUCUAAGUGGGGGAGGAGGAGGGUCACCCAAAUUGGAUCACAGCUUUCAUUUGCAUUGCUUACAAAACGGAUACCCCGCAAGCUGACAGAAGCUGCUGUGUGUGUGUGAGUGUGUGUGUGUAUGUGAAUGUAUACAACAAUUUAGACAGUGGCAGGCUGUAUUUGAAGCCUAUGGAAUGGCUAUUCGUUAAGGAGAAGAUGGGAGCACACACUCACUGGGUUCCCAGGGGAAGCUGACUUUGAUGUUGCCCGGGAGCAGGGCUGAUUCUGUGAGGUGUAACUAGAGACAGGAUUUACCAGGAGAGUCUGCUUCCUGGAGAAUGUUGAAAUAUCUGAUGCCGUUUACUUUGAAACCCGUAGAUCAUUCUCUUUGCCUUAAAAGUUAUUUCAACAUCUUCAAAACAACCUGUCCAGGAGUGGGGGCUGGGGAGAGCGCUUGCAGCACGACAACGGUGUGCAAUCCCUGAUCAUCCCUGGAAGACUGACUCCUACUCGGGACCCUGUUCCUCCUCCUCCCGGCGCCUGUCCACAUCUGCGCUGACUCCCACUCGGGACCCCUGUCCCUCCUCCUCCCGGCGCCUGCCCGCAUCUGCGGUGUUGGUUGCUUUUUGUGGUGUCCACACGUUUCCUUUGUGUUCUGGUUCUGCAUGGGAAGAGCCCUGCAGCUUGGGGCUUUCCAUCCAUCUCUUUCUUUUUCCCUUAUUUUUGGUUGGUGACUCUUGGCGGCUCUCUGUGGGGACACUGAUGCUCUCCAAGAAGGUACUUCUUGAAUCAGUGACCCUUAUUGUCUUUUUCUGAUGAGGGUCUAAGGUUUUCCUUCAGUGAAUCAGUGCUGUCUUAUCUGGAACAUUUUAGGGAACUGGAAUUUGCAUUUAUCCCCUUGGCUUUAUAUUAUUGAAAAAGAACUUAGGUCUUUUGCUGCCAAAACAGUUGUUACCAAACCAUAUUUGAUCACGAGAGUAGUGGAACAAUUUAUUAUGAAGGGGGAAAACUCAGCACCUUUCUUUCCCUGGUUGUCCUGGCUUUUGUGGGCUUGCGUCCAGGGCACCCAGCUGGGCUCUGGGCUCUUUCUCUCCCCAGAUAAGGUCUCCUCCUGGGUGCAUUCGGGAAGUUAUUUGGAGGGUUCUUCCAGAUUUUUGAAUGCCCUUACAUUUUCGAGCCCUCACGGCAGGCUUAGGAGAGGAUUUACCUCUUUUAUUGCUGAGCUAGGGAGGGGUCCAGCCUCCACAGGGAGGUGACACGGCGUGGCCCCAGCCUGCCCAUUCAGGAACUGGACCCACUUCAGGGUCAGAAGAGGACAACUGAGGUCUCAUCUGCAAAGUCCCGGGGCCUUGCUGAGGCAGGAGAGCCUGUUGCAGGUCUGACCCUUCACAUGUUGCUUGUAGGGAGUGGGCUACCCACCCCUCACCACCCCGAGAACAGCCUGAGCCCGGGGCGCAUCUCUGUCUCUGUGUGGAGAGACACUGCCGCUUCUGUUCCCUGGGAAGCCAGUGCCAUUUUCAGCAUUUAGGGGGUUCCUGGUGAGGGCUCAGGAGAGAUCUGGGCCCAGAGCCAGCCACACUCCUUGUGUUGAGUAAGACUCAUCCCAUCUCUGAUCUGUGACACGAGGAGAGGAGCCCCUCACUCACCCGCCACAGCUCAGGGUGGUGAUGCGGCACCAUUGGAGUGAGCGGCCCCGGGGGACUGGGGAGGCUCUGGCCGGCGUAGUCCUUGCCGCCAGCCUUCACAGCGGGUUCUCUGAGGGUCUUUAUGCACAGGGGCUCUGUCACUUAGCUCUGGCCCCCCCUCUGCCCCUGAGGCAUGACUUUGGGCAACGCAGCAUCCAAGCCUCAGUUUCCCCAUCUCUAAGAUGAGUUGACAACAGAGCCUCUCUGGUGGGUGCCGUGGGCCACAGGGUGCCCAGAACGCAGUCCCCGUGCCUCUGUUUCUGUGCUGCCUCCACUCACCGUCAGCCUUCAUUCGGAGUAGGUGCGCAUGCUGUGCAAAGCCCUUCCACACACCUGAUCUCAGUUGCUCUCUGUGCAAAAGUCAGAGAGGCUUUCCCUGCAUUUCCUGUUUGAACAGUGUCCUGGCCUCCAUCUUUAGCUUUGACAGUGUUUACCAUGGGGGUGCUGAGGGUGAGUUCUUGUGUAUGUGCACAUCUUUCUGGUGGAGUGGAGGCCUCUUGAGGACAGGAACCUUGUGGGUCUACCUCCUUUUCUUCGGAGCUCAGCUGACUGCCUGGCAAACAGCAGAUGCUUUUGGUGUCUGGUGAGUGAAUGGGGGGUGGGGAGCUGGUCCUGUGACCCUGGUGAGGCGGGACAAACUUGUCUUCCUCACACCCAUCUUACUUCCUCUUAUGAGGAAACCCAGAGAGAUGAGGGGUCUUGCCCAAGGAAGGGGUGUCCAUAGUCAGCUCUGCCUUCUGCUCACCCAGAAUAAAGACCUGGGGACCCCGCGAGGGUCAUGGCCAAGUGGAAUGGACUCCUGGCAUUUGAGGGCUUCCCGACUGCAGCCCUCAGGCAGCCAUGGCUGUCCCAAGUCCAGCGGGCCUUUGCUCGGGUCAUGGCUGGGAUGUCUGGCCCUUCCUGACAGGAGGCUGCUGGGCUCCUGUCUACUUGGGGACGCCUCAUGCAGGAGCUGGUGUGGGGGUGGGCAGGGGGGCGGUGGCUUCUUCCUUUCUCUUUCCCUUUCCUCUACCUUUUCCCCUCUCCCCAGAGGAAAUGGUAGCAGGAUUUCUUUUAAGAGGAUGCUGCUGUAUUUUGCCAGCGGGUGGAAGGUGGCGGUAUUAGCUCCCGUGAGCUGCACGUGGACCCCUGUGUGAAGCGUAGCAGGGCACAGAGCAGGCGAGACGUUUGCAUCUCACAGCGGGAGGGCCGGCGACAUCACAUGAAGUGACAGGCAGGCCCUUGGAAGCCGGUGCUUAGAUCCUUAAUUAGUUCACACGUCGACUGAAUUUUCAAGUGAAUGAAUUUUAAUUACAUCUCAGGUUAAAAAAAAAAAAAGGCGCCAGUGAUCGAGGACUCGUCACUGGGCUCUGUUGCUCCUGAAGUUUCCUAGCCCACAACACACCAACACUGCCAAGGGCUCUUCUGGAUUCAAGGUGAAACACAUGUGCCAUAAAUCUUGGAGCUCUGAAUGUUUGGAAAGGGCCCGACUGUGAGAAGAAGUAACACACCGUCCCGUGCAGAUGGCUGGCUCUGAGGAGGAGUUCAUGGGAGCUUGGGGACACUCUUGCCUCUAGUUCUAGGAAGCUGGGCCACUUCUGAAGUAAUGGCAAUAUCAAUAAAGUAAUGGUCUUUAUCAUAGAA